AUGUUUAGUAUCAGAAGACAGUAUCAAAUACUGUGCACUGAUUGUGAAAUAAAAUUAUAAACCUUGUAGAAGAUUCUGGUUUUCAUGAAAUUCGUAAACAUGAAUUUGAUAAUUGUUUAAAUCACAAAGGCUUUGACAAAUGAGGAAAUGCCACUUAGCUAGAUAAUUGAAGAAUCAUGACAGGAUAGGCAUCUCAAAAGAAUAAUUGUAAUAUUAAAGGAUUAAGAGGUCCUUGGGGAAACAGAUGAAACCCUUGAACAUUAUGCAAAAAUGACCCAUUUUAUGAUCAUACCGAAACAUUCAAAUGUGAAAAUGAAGGUGUUCUAAUAGAAUCUUGCCAGAAAAAUUACUCCAAGGGGCUCCCCAUUAACACUGGAUUUAUUCUUUGGUCAUUCUAAGAAUUAGCACUUCUGUAACUGUAUCCCAGAUUUUGUAAAAGAUCCCAGAUUUUGUAAAAUAUUUAUUGGUUCUUUUUAUUCAAGAUAAAAAAUCCCCAAUCUUUUUUAAACUAUAUGAUAUGGAAGUGUUGUGCCUUUUUAAAGUGAAUUUAUCUGAAGUGGCCAGUAGUCCUUAGUCACUUUCUAUGUAAUAUCUAAGAAAUUUUUGUUGUUAAGGACUUUAUAAUUUGUUACUGUAUUCAAAAGGAAAUAGUGCUUUAUGCUCUGAUUCUUAAUUUAAAAACAACAAAAAGCAAAAAAGUCCCAAAGAAACCCAGAAUGUUAUCAUUAUUAAAUGCUGUACCUCAUGAACUUGAAUCUGUGAAGCAGAGUGGGAAGGGCCAGCCAGCUCUUGAAAGUGGUAGACUAUGCAAGCAACAGUAGAGACCUCAAGUGUUCAGGAUGGUGUGAAAAGGACUUGUAAUGAAGUGUUGGUAUUUUCAUUAUUCACAAAGGUAAAACGAUUAAACCAUUUUGAUAUUUGAAUAUUUAAUAUUUGAGGGACAGCAUUGAACUGAUUAUAUGUCUACAACGACUUGCUUUUUAGUUCAUUGGAAUGUCAGGAAUACUUUUUGAGCAAGGAAAAAAGUCAUUCAUAUUUCUUUUGGCCAAUGCAUUGCUUACAAUGAGUUACAAGGCACUAAUAGUUCUGGAUCCUUGGGUGGUCUUGAUGUUCGCAGACGAAUUCCUAUAAAGCUCAUCUCCAAACAAGCAAACAAAGCGAAACCUGCACCGCGAACUCAAAGAACUAUAAACAGGAUGCCUGCAAAGGCUCCACCUGGUGAUGAAGAAGGAUUUGAUUAUAAUGAAGAAGAACGGUAUGACUGUAAAGGGGGUGAGCUGUUUGCAAAUCAGCGAAGAUUUCCUGGACACCUUUUUUGGGACUUUCAGAUAAACAUCUUAGGUGAAAAGGAUGAUACACCAGUUCAUUUCUGUGACAAGUGUGGAUUGCCUAUUAAAAUCUAUGGGAGAAUGAUUCCAUGCAAGCAUGUUUUUUGCUAUGACUGUGCUAUUUUACAUGAAAAAAAGGGAGAUAAGAUGUGUCCAGGCUGUAGUGAUCCUGUGCAGCGAAUUGAGCAGUGUACACGAGGUUCUCUCUUCAUGUGUAGCAUUGUUCAAGGGUGCAAGAGAACAUAUUUGUCUCAGAGAGACUUACAGGCUCAUAUCAACCAUCGCCAUAUGAGAGCUGGAAAACCUGUUACCCGUGCUUCACUUGAAAAUGUUCAUCCUCCUAUUGCCCCACCACCAACUGAAAUCCCUGAGCGUUUUAUAAUGCCACCAGACAAGCACCAUAUGAGCCAUAUUCCGCCAAAGCAGCACAUCAUGAUGCCACCACCUCCUUUGCAACAUGUGCCACAUGAGCACUAUAAUCAGCCACAUGAGGAUAUUCGUGCUCCUCCAGCAGAAUUGUCCAUGGCUCCACCUCCACCUCGAUCGGUCAGUCAGGAAACCUUUCGUAUUUCAACAAGAAAACACAGCAAUUUAAUAACCGUCCCUAUUCAGGAUGACUCAAAUUCAGGUGCUAGAGAACCACCACCUCCUGCCCCAGCACCUGCUCACCAUCAUCCUGAAUAUCAGGGUCAACCAGUGGUAUCGCACCCUCAUCAUAUUAUGCCUCCACAGCAACAUUAUGCACCACCCCCACCUCCUCCACCACCAAUAAGCCAUCCAAUGCCACAUCCUCCCCAGGCUGCAGGUACUCCUCACUUGGUAUAUAGCCAAGCUCCACCUCCACCAAUGACCUCUGCUCCACCACCAAUAACCCCUCCCCCUGGACAUAUUAUUGCCCAGAUGCCACCUUAUAUGAAUCAUCCUCCUCCAGGACCUCCCCCACCUCAACAUGGUGGUCCACCUGUAACUGCACCCCCUCCUCACCAUUAUAAUCCUAACUCAUUACCCCAGUUCACUGAAGAUCAAGGAACUCUGAGCCCUCCAUUUACACAACCAGGGGGAAUGAGUCCUGGUAUAUGGCCUGCACCAAGAGGGCCACCACCACCUCCACGAUUGCAGGGUCCGCCUUCUCAAACCCCACUUCCUGGACCACAUCAUCCAGAUCAGACAAGAUAUAGACCGUAUUACCAAUGAUAAUAGUAUUUUGAAUGGAAGAUAUGAGGGGGAAAAAAACUUAUGUGUAGUCAAUCUUUUAAGCUUUGACUGUUUUGGGAAGGAAGAGUACCUCUUAUCGAGGUAGUAUAAAACACAUAGGGUCUUGUUUCUUAAAAUGGUUUUAAAUCUUGACCUUAAGAUUGAUUUCAAGUACCAUACUGUAGUACAGAUAAGUGGCUCAGUUGAGCACAGCUAUAUUUUAACAUCUCUUUGUUCCCCUAGUUUAGUAAAUUGACCCAGAGGUGACCAUUUGUAAAAAAUUUGAAAAAAUUUUUCAUUGUUUUACUUCAAAAGUAUUGUUUUGUUAAACCCAACGUUUAGUUUUUCUUGUGAUACAUUUUGUUAACCUGUGUAAAAGGAUUAAAUUUCAAUAUGGUUGUAAAAAUGCUAUUUUUAUGUGAAUUUAAGUGCAGCCACAUACUGUUUUUUAAACCAUAUGUUUUACCACUAAUUUCCCAAAGUUAUAAUAAAAUCCUGAAAGUAAAAAUCUACUAGAAUUUGCUGUAAGGCAGACUGUUAAAUGAUAGAGAAUUAUUUCACAUUUUAGGCACUGAAAUGUUGAGGUUUCGAGGUAUAGUAAGUAUACAAUGCACUUCACUUGGAUGCCUUUUCAUUUUUAGGCAGCCUCAGGAGCACCAAAAUACAUUGGAAUUCUAGUACUAAGAUAUAUUUGUUCGUAAUGUUAAAAGACAUUACUAAUUAUUUGGAAAGAGAUGGCCAAAAUAAUCAACUCUACAGGCUUCAAGCUGGUGGGGGAAUGCUGUUACUCAUUAAUGCUUUUUUACUGAAUGGUCGGAAUCACAUAUGCACCACACAUACUGAUCUUAAGUAACAUUAUUUUAUAGAACUGUUUAAAUGGGUUUAAAUGGUGUUCUUUAGAUGAAAUGUGUUCUGUUUUGUUCAUUGUCUUAAACUGAAUAGGGCUGAAUAGGCUUUAUGUAAUUCUUCAUUUCAUGGUAGAGUUUGAUGCUGUGUUUAAGUGGGUUCUUGUUUAUAGGAUUUUCAACUACAGUUUGAAUGCCAUGGAGGAAUUUGAAUAAUAUAUUAAUGAAGGACAUAUUCUUGUAAUCACAAAUUUGCAUUUGCUCAGGUUUCAUUGCUGUGUGAUAGGAUUUUUCCUCUAACUUGAAAUUUAAAAACUUUUAUUUCCUAUUCCUUUUGUCGGUAAAGCAGUCUGAAUUUGGAACAUUUUAUCAUGGAGUCAACAGUGAAGACUACCAGAUAAUUUUGUAUUGGAGAAGAGGAAAUAACAGCUAAAUUGUGGAUUUCAGUGCUUUACAUGGUGCCUUUCGAGUCAGCUUUUACAUUAUAGGGGCUUGUUAUAGUUUAGCUAAGAUGACCACUUAACAGUUUAUACAGAACUCAUAUGUAUAAAUCAACAUUCUUAGGAUAUUAUUUAUAUCCUUUGAAUAAAUCCCUGUGAAGUUUUUCCUCCCCACUAAAAUGGUGCAUAAUAAAACAUGAAAUAUGUAGUAUGCAGAUAUCAUUUAUUAGAUAGUUUGUAGUGUAUACAUUUAGAACAUACUUCUUUUGACAAAGGGUGAUCUGAUUGCUAAUUUACCAUUUUAUUCUGUCAGGUACAGGUGAAACAAAUUCUCAUCUUGAAUGAUCAGAUGCAAAAUCAUUUCUGAACCCUAGAGCAGAAGUUAGAAAUAACAAAAUGGCCGUUUCAACCUUGACUGGCCAAAAAUAACUAAUAAACUUUUUUGUUUUAAGUCAGGCAAGUGAUUUUCUACAUUUAGCAGUUUGAAAGUCCAGUGUUAAUGCAAUAUUUCUAGUGAGAAAUGCUUGUUAUUAAAAGCAUGGGAGUGAUAGUGUGAAAUGGUGGUGAGUGCUUCUAUCAUAUUACUGUAGGUACUUGGACUGGUGCAAACUUGAUUCCUUUUCAUCCCCCUGUUUAGGAGCUAUUAAAAUAUUACUGUUAAAAAUCCAAACCAUUCUUUGUUCCAUGUAAUAAGAAAAUAGCCAAAAUCACUUUAGAGCUUCUCAACUAUUUAUGAAGAGCUAUCCUGCUUUUAUUGAAAGUCACUAGAGUUGAAUGUGGUAAGAAACCACUUAGCCUAUGUAUUGGACGAGAAAAUCAGUAUCAUGAUAAAAUUUUGAAUUAAGAGAACCCUUGUAGAGUUUUUAAAAAAUGAUUUAUUUUCAAUUAGGUUUAAGAAAUCUAUGUUAUGCAGGGAGGCAUAUCAGAUGAAUGUUGUAGCAGACAAAAGUUUUAAAUCGUGUUAGACUUGAAUUCAUCAAUUGUUUGAAUGAGGGUGGGUGGGUAGAAGGAUAACAAAAUUACUGUUAGUGUUUCUUUCCUUACGGAAAAAGAUGUGAAUCCCAGCCUUAUUUCAGGGAAGCCUUUGAAGCUAUGAUGGACAUAAGUCUAAAUUAAAUGUAUGUAUGUUUCAUUAUAUUGCUCUUAAGACUACUGAGGUGGCAGUUUAAUUCUUAAAAACAAUAAAAUGGAAGCAUAAAUACUA